GAGUUCAUCUCCAAGUCACUUUUUGUAAACGCCCCGCACAGCCUGGACCGGCCUGCCCCCGCCCAGCGAGCCUCAGGGGCCCAGCCGACAGCCAGGCUCACGCGCCCUUGAAAUCUGCCGGUACUCGCUCUGCGGGCUGGGCUGGGAGAUGACGAGGACCCCGGUGGGGUCUGCCCGCACCCGGCCAAAGCCCAGGAAGCUCGGGCCCCAGCGAGGAAAGGCGCUCCAAGCCUCCUCGCGGCUUUCAGAGGAACAGAAUCCCCAGCCCUGGUGAAGAAGAGGAUGCCUGAUGCGUGCACCCUGGGAAGGGCUGGAAUCGGUCUCCCCAAGAUGUGCCUUCACAUGGCUGUCCGGCAUUCGAAGGCUCAGAAAACAGGCAAGAAAAUGCGGGCGGGAAAGCUGGCAGAAUGAUUACUUUCAGGUCCCCUCCAGGCUUCUGCGGAAAAGCCAGGGGCUUCGGGCUGGAGAUAGAGGAAUCUAGGGAGAGAACAGAAUCCUCUCCUUGCCGGCCCAGCCAGAGGUGGGUGAACCGGGCGCUCCAGGAAACGGUGCGGGGCGCCCUGAUUUACUUCUCAACCUUCGGAGGUAGGCUGGUUGCUGGCGAGGUCGGGAUCCUCUCUGAACAGGGCAUACUGUGCCUAGGUUUUGUGGACGCCAGGGCCGGUUCCUUUUCUCCCCGCGGCAUUGGGGCGACGCAGGGCCCCCGGCUUAGUGACCUUGGGGCGGCGCUCACCUCCAAAGGCCAGGGUGGUGGGCUGGGCAGAACUCACUGCCUCUUUGCCCCAGUUUUCCAGGGUCCCGCAGCUGCAAUUCAGCAGCCACCGGCGCCUCCUGACCGUGGUCCCACCGUAGCGCCGCCUGCGGAUACGGUUCCAGUGAACCGCCGAUUGAGCGCAGUCUCAGCUCCCGCGCCUCCUCGCAGCCUGGCCCCGCGCCUCGGAGGUCCCGACAGCCGGCGCGAGCAAUCUACACGGCUCUGAUACAGACGCUUUUCUCCCCAGGGCCGGGAAUCCUGCAACAGCGGCAGAAGCCGCCCGCGCCUCGGGCUUCCGGCGGCCCAGCUCUACUAGGGAAGCGUCGCGGCUGCUCUGAGGCAGGCAGCGCUUCGCUAGAACCACUCAGCUCGUCCCGCGCCGCCGCCGGCUGCCUGAACCAGGUUCCGCUGUCCCCUUUCCUAGCGGGACCCCGAAACACCCGGCGGCUUCCCGCUCCUGAGCGGGAGAGAAUAGAGCUUGCUGCAACCCUCUGCUUGGAGGGAUGGCCUCUGCGGUGCUUGGCUAGCAAAGGGAAGCUUCACUGUGUCUAUUAGUACAUCCCCAUACACUCCACGCCUCAACAACUGUCAGCACUCACUCCCUCCCGGCCCCUCACAGGGCCCUUUGCACCCACACCUCAGGGACUCGGUGUCCCUCCACUCAGGUCACGUUACUCCAUCCACUUCUCUCUCCUUCUCCCUCUGUCAACUCCAAAUCCCCUCUAGUUCUCCCUCCCCUCCUACUUCUCUCACACUCACCAGCUACACGUACUAAUUCAGAUUUUGCACAUGUUGGUGGAAAACAUGUCAAGCCAAUGUGCAGACCCUAAGGCUUUUCACACGCUGCUCACUUUCGCAUCUCACGGUGCAGAAGGACCAAUGGGCUCCAGGUUUACAAGCCUGACUCCGAGAAGCCUGUUGAUUCUCUGAUGUCCUUGGCCUGUGAUUCGGGUGACUGGGCUGCCACCUGGGUGUUUUCAUGAUGGGACUGCCGCACAGACCACAGAGAAGCUCAGGUACUGAGCACGUUCCAGAUACACUUUAACAUGCACAGGCCACUCACACAGGCUUUAUCUCUGUCUCGAAACUCUGCUGAGUUUGCUGCUCAGACCAACAAGGUGCAGCAGCAGACACCCACAUAGCACCAGGUCUGAAGCCAGUGGGUAUUAGUCUGCCUGGUUGGGAUUAGCAAAGUCAGUUACUCACAUAUGUGCUUGGGAGAGAAUAGGGGAGUGGAGAGAGAGAGAGAGAUAUUGAGGAAGAGGAAAGAGAAGCGACCUCCUACUCUGGGAAGAACUCACACAUGAGAGCUGUUUCCUGUUGUUAAGUGUCUCACUGAGCUCCCCUCUUUCUCCCCCAGGAAGGGCUUGAGAGGCAGUAGACCAGAGCUCUGGGCUCCUCUUUACCUUGCUGAUGUUGGGGUAUGAGUCCUCCAACACCAUUUUGUCCCAAGGAGUAUGUGCCCCAUCGUCAAUCAGGCAGAAUGCAGGGCAGUUGUCGGCCUUUUUCAUGGUGGAGGCCAACUGGGAAAAAGGCAGAAGGGUCUGGGUCCUGGGCCAAGUGAGGCCCUCUUCCCUCCAAAGACCCGUGGGAUGCUCUCAGAGGCGGAUUCUAGGGUGGUGGGAGCUGCUGACAAGUUUCCUCUGAUAUCCCUCAUGACAUCUAUGGCCCAAAGCCAUUUUGUUCAGCUCUGAACAGUGAGUGCCUUGCCAGUAGGCCUCAGGCUUGCUGGGGAACAUGAUGUGUUCUUAAAAGUUGCCUUGUUGCCUUUCUCCACACCCAGACUGUAAGCGCUGAUGGGCAGAGACUCUGCCCUCCACUUCUCACUCAGUGCUCCCCACCAGGAUGGGCUUAAUGCCUUUUAAUAGAAUUAGAAAAUGGUUCUGCUGGACAGAAUUGGGAAAUGCCACUUUCCUUAUAAUGAAGUUAUAAUGAAGUUAGAAUUUCCAAGAAAGGGACUGUAGCUGAGGAAAAGCGGUUUGAUCAUUGACAGCCAGCUCAGGAUCUGAGAGUUCUUUGCCAUUUGGGGUUAUUAUAGCUGCAUGGCCAUGGUGCUGAACCUUAGGCAAGGGCAAGGACACCUCCCUAGUUCCCAGUCAUGGUGAGGACCUGUCUGAAACAUUCAAACUAGACUUUACUGGAAACAGAGAAGUCUCUGCAUUCAGGGCAGCUGGCUUGCAAGGUAAGGCCUGCAGUCUCCACCCGCACGCUAACCCAUGAGGGGAUGCCAGAGAGAGCCCUUCCCCCUUGGUCCUCAUUCCUGGCUCAAUUUUCUCCCACAAAGCGGGCACUUUCUAAAGAUGAUAGGCAACUGCCAUGGAGGAAGGCAGUUUUAGAUGCCUAGCUGGCACAAAGUCCAGAGGAAGGGAGGGAGAAGGGCUGAGUUUUGUAUUACUGUUCUACCUUUGGAGAUUUUCCUCAUGCCAAGAUAGGGUGUGUGUGUGUGUGUGUGUGUAUGUGUGUGUGUAUGUGUGCACUAUAACUUUAUGAAACACUUUUUUUUUUUUUGAGACAGGGUCUCACUCUGUUGCCCAAGCUGGAGUGCAGUGGUGCAAUCUUGGCUUACCGCAGUCUCCACCUCCCAGGCUCAAGUGAUCCUCCCAUCUCAGCCUCAGCCUCCCAAGUAGCUGGGACUAUGGGUGUGAGCCAACACACUCAGCUAAUUUUUUUUUUUUUUUUUUGGUAUUUUUGGUAGAGACAGGGUUUUACCAUGUGGGCCCAACUGGUCUUGAGCUCCUGAGCUCAGGGUGAUUUGCCUGCUUCAACUUCCCAAAGUGUUGGGAUUACAGGUGUGAGCCACCAUGCCCAGUCAGUUUUUUAUUUUUUAUUUAAACAGUUUUGGGGGAACAGGUGGUUUUUGCUUACAUGGAUAAGUUCUUUAAUGGUAAUUUCUGAGAUUUUGGUGCACUUGUCACCCGAGCAUUGUACACGGUACCCAGUGUGUAAUCUUUUAUCCCUCAUCCCCCUCCUACGCUUCCCCCCCCGAGUCCCCAUUAUAUAAUUCUUUUUUUCUUCUUUUUGAGACAGAGUCUCACUCUGUUGCCCAGGCUGGAGUGCAGUGGCAUGAACUUGGCUUACUGCAGCCUCCUGAGUUCAAGUGAUUCUCCUGCCUGAACCUCCUGUGUAGCUGGGACUACAGGCAUGCACCACCAUGCCCAGCUAAUUUUUGUAUUUUUUGUAGAGAUGGGGUUUCACCAUGUUGGCCAGGCUAGUCUUGAACUCCUAACCUCAAGUGAUCUGCCUAUUUUGGCCUCCCAAAGUGUUGGGAUUACAGGCGUGCGCCACUGCGCCUGGUCCAUUAUGUCAUUCUUAUGCCUUUGCAUCUUCAUAGCUUAGCUCCCACUUAUAAAUGAAAACACAGGAUAUUUGGUUUUCCAUACUUGAGUUACUUCACUUAGUAUAAUGGUCUCCAGCUCCAUCCAGGUUGCUGUGAAUGCCAUUAUUUUGUUCCUUUUUAUGGCUGAGUAGUAUUCCAUGGUGUAUAUAUAUCACAUUUUCUUUAUCCACUCAUUGGUUGAUGGGCAUUUAGCCUUGUUCCAUAUUUUUGUAUGCAGUAUAACUUACAGAUGGUAAACAAUAUACAGCUUGAUGUAUUCUGACAUGUAAUGCAGUAUGUAACCACCACCUGGAUCAAGAUAUGGAGCAUUUCUGGCACUUCAGAAGGUUCCUUCAUAUCUUUUUCCAAUCAAUAUUGCCUCAAAAGGGAAACCAUAUUUGGAUUUCUAUCACCAUAAAUAACCUUUGCCUGCCUUGAGCCUCGUAUAAAUGGAGCAUAUAGCAUGUAUGCCUUUAUGUCUAGUUUUUUCUGUGCAACAUAUUUUUAAUAUUCACUGGUCUUGUUGCAUGUGUCAGACAUUUAUUUCUUUUUAUUGCUGUGUAAUAUUCUAGUAUUUGCUUAUCCAUCCAUAUGUUGAGGGACAUUUGUUUCCAGUUUUUGGAUAUCAUAAAUAAAGCUGCUGUGCACAUUGUUGUA